CUCUUCCGCUGCGUGCCGGACCAUGGCGCAGGGGCAGCGCAAGUUUCAGGCGCACAAACCCGCAAAGAGUAAGACGGCAGCGGCAGCCUCUGAAAAGAAUCGGGGCCCAAGAAAAGGCGGUCGUGUUAUCGCUCCCAAGAAGGCGCGCGUCGUGCAGCAGCAAAAGCUCAAGAAGAACCUAGAAGUCGGAAUCCGGAAGAAGAUCGAACAUGACGUGGUGAUGAAAGCCAGCAGCAGCCUGCCCAAGAAGCUGGCACUGCUGAAGGCCCCAGCCAAGAAGAAAGGGGCAGCUGCCGCCACCUCCUCCAAGACACCUUCCUGAGGACGCUGGCCCCAGUGCAGGCCAACAUCCCACCCCCUACCUCCAUAUGGGACCUUGCAAGUCAUCCCACAGGCUGCACUGUCAGGAAGAGGACCCUGUCCCCCAGCACUGGGCUUCACCUAGAACUUCAGUGGGGGCCAAGGGUGCUGAGAACCCAGCAAUGACCAGGAAGAUACAGUCACUAACUUCAUCUGUCCCCGUGCCCCUUCCCAGGUCCUGCCUCCACAGGUUUAACCCAGAACAAUAAACCUGGCUUUGUCAUCCCUCUUGCAGUCCUGUGUUCGGGUGAGCAGGCCAGGUGAGCCCACAAGUCUCCAUGAGUGACGUGGCCUGGCGUGCUCCACCCCACCCCACCGCCUUUAGCAACCAUGUGCCCAGGGGACAGCUGGGCUUCUACACCUCUGGCCCUGAGCCUGAGAGCCGGGAAAGAGUCUUUUCUCCAUUUAACCCCGGGUGACUCACUCCCUGGCCAGUCCUCACCCCUGGGGACACAACCAGAGUCAAGCUGGACAUCAGUAGGUCAGAUGCCACCUCACAGGACCAAGGUGCCGAUUAAACCGGAAUACAUUCAGAAA